GUAGUUUCGGCCGAGGGUGGGCUCCGCGGUCGCCGGUUUCUCUUCCCAGCUCUGCCCUCGCUUGCUGGCCGGUCUCCGGGGUCAGCGCGGGGCCACCAUCCAGCCCCUUGGGGCCCGCCCCAAGCAGCUGUCGAGGACGCACUCAGCCUGCGCAGCCAUGGCCUCGGCAGGGGCGGAGAGGCGGCCGGGGGUCCAGGAGGCGACGGUCGUGGGGCAGGGACAGCUCACGGAGGAGCCCGGCAGCGCUCAGACCUCCGAGGUGACCGUCAGGCUGUUUAACCUUCAAACACAGGGCCGCAGCGCUCUGAGAGGUGGAACUGAGCGCCCCGACCCGCUAACUGCCAGGCUGGGCCCUCCAGGCGGGGAGGGGCACAGGCUGGUGUCCUUAUUCCCGUUUCGGUGUCUAACGUUAGGUGUUCAGUGACGGAUCCCUAUGUCCUUUGCCCGGCCAUGGUGACCGAUGGCCUGUGUGUCAUCUCUAGUGUCCAGUGGCGGGAGACCAGUUCCUGGUGCCUGCCCAUGAGGCCCGCGGAACCCAGAGUGAAGACCAGCGCCCAGCAGGCGCAGCUUCGGAGUCGGAGCUCCAGGAGGAAGGACCCAAGCUGGGGGAGGAGCGGCCCAAGCCGCAUGCCGGGGCGCUAGAGGAGAGAGGCCCCAGGCCCGUGGUCUCCAUUGUGAGGCCCCGUCAUGGUCCAAAGAGAAAGCCUGUCAAGUGAGGGGGCUCUCGGGGGGAAGGAGCUGCAGCCCCGGGGUUGGGGCACACACCACAGUAGGAUUCCUAAAUCCUGCACUCCUGCAGGGAGGAUUCUCGUCCCCAGCCACUACCAUCACUCUCCUCCCGUUCCUCAAGAGCCCCCGUGUAGGGAGCAGCAGGAGAGUGGGAGCUUCAGGGCUUGUAGGGGCCUGGGCUCACUGGCCUCUAAGCCUCUUGGGCCUGGGGUCUCAUUGACCAGGAACGGGACAGGCGUCGAGCCCUGGGGCUGUGGGCAGGCUGGGCUAUUCCCUGGGCCAGGGAAUGGGAGCCAGGGCUGGAGCCUGGCUCAAGUCUCUUGUCCCUGGCUCAGGUCUCUCAGCCUCCCGGGCCUUCGUGCCCAUCUUAAGGCUGAAGCUGAGCUGCCACCCAAGCUGCCGCUGCAGGAGGAGGAGCCAGAGGACAGCCAGAGUGAGCCCUCACCAUCUGCCAAACAGCACAAAAAAGCCAAGAAGCGCAAGAGCCUGGGGGCUCCCGUGCUCCACGCUGUGGCCAGCAUGGUGUCUGCACCCUUAGAGACAUUGAGGCUGGAGCCCUCUGCCCUGCCCUGGGUCUUUGCAGGAAAGGCCCAGCGCCUGCGGCCGCUGUACCAGUACGUCAACUAUUGCAACCCUGAGCUGAACCAGGCAGGGAAGGGGGACGGGGAGGCUGAGGUGGAGGCAGAGGCAGAGCUGGCCCCGGUUCCCGAGGAGGGAGGUGUGGAGCAACUGCAGGCCUUGCUGCCCUUGGCAGGUGAGCUGGGCCCAGGCCUCGCUUUGCCCUGUCCCAGUCCACUAGUGACCCCCACCCAUGCCCUGGCUCCCCUCGGAGAGGAGGCUGGAGAGGAGCCUGGGGGCUUGCCCAGCUUGGGGGUGAGUGACCACAAGGCCGAGGUGGAUAAGUCAACCCAGGUGGACAUCGACAAGAUGCUGAGUGUCUGCACUGCUCCACUUGUCCCCCCGCUCUCUCCUCAGUACAAGUGACUGUCCCGCCCCACUGGUGGCUCCCCUCCUUCCACGCCUGAAUUUGGCUUCAGGCUUCCUGUGGGCCUAGGCCCUCUGGUGGCGGGGGCAAAUUUGGCACCUGCCCCCACUUGGGACUUUGGUCUUGCUGAAAAUAAAUAUUUUUCUUUUUCAAA